AGCAGGCUCAGAAGGUCCAGAAAUCAGGGGAAGGAGACCCCUAUCUGUCCUUCUUCUGGAAGAGCUGGAAAGGAAGUCUGCUCAGGAAAUAACCUUGGAAGAUGGUGGCCACGAAGACCUUUGCUCUGCUGCUGCUGUCCCUGUUCCUGGCAGUGGGACUAGGAGAGAAGAAAGAGGGUCACUUCAGCGCUCUCCCCUCCCUGCCUGUUGGAUCUCAUGCUAAGGUGAGCAGCCCUCAACCUCGAGGCCCCAGGUACGCGGAAGGGACUUUCAUCAGUGACUACAGUAUUGCCAUGGACAAGAUUCACCAACAAGACUUUGUGAACUGGCUGCUGGCCCAAAAGGGGAAGAAGAAUGACUGGAAACACAACAUCACCCAGAGGGAGGCUCGGGCGCUGGAGCUGGCCAGUCAAGCUAAUAGGAAGGAGGAGGAGGCAGUGGAGCCACAGAGCUCCCCAGCCAAGAACCCCAGCGAUGAAGAUUUGCUGCGGGACUUGCUGAUUCAAGAGCUGUUGGCCUGCUUGCUGGAUCAGACAAACCUCUGCAGGCUCAGGUCUCGGUGACUCUGACCACACCCAGCUCAGGACUGGAUUCUGCCCUUCACUUAGCACCUGCCUCAGCCCCACUCCAGAAUAGCCAAGAGAACCCAAACCAAUAAAGUUUAUGCUAAGUCGAGCCCAUUGUGAAAAUUUAUUAAAAUGACUACUGAGCACUAA